AGACUUUAGUUCGGCCCUAGGAUUUGGUAGCCCCGAAGUGUGGGCUCUCUCCAGUACCAGACUCAUUUCAGUACCAGCCUUUGGGAAGUCGUGUGAAUACCUCGGUCUCUUAGCCACAGGGAUAGAAUGGCGGCCUGACGGAGCCGCGGCGCCGGCGAAGUCGCUGAGGCGCGAGCUGGAACCCCCAGACCAGCUCAAACGGGAGCCAAAACUCGAAGCUUGGAAGAAUUAGCAGGAAAUGGCGGAUGAGGCGUUGUUUUUGCUUCUCCAUAACGAGAUGGUGUCUGGAGUGUACAAGUCCGCGGAGCAGGGGGAGGUGGAAAACGGACGAUGUAUUACUAAGCUGGAAAACAUGGGGUUUCGAGUGGGACAAGGAUUGAUAGAAAGGUUUACAAAAGAUACUGCAAGGUUCAAGGAUGAGUUAGAUAUCAUGAAGUUCAUUUGUAAAGAUUUUUGGACUACGGUAUUCAAGAAACAAAUCGACAAUCUAAGGACAAAUCAUCAGGGCAUCUAUGUACUUCAGGACAACAAAUUUCGCCUGCUUACUCAGAUGUCUGCAGGAAAACAGUAUUUAGAACAUGCAUCUAAGUAUUUAGCAUUUACGUGUGGCUUAAUCAGAGGUGGCUUAUCAAACUUGGGAAUAAAAAGUAUUGUAACAGCUGAAGUGUCUUCAAUGCCUGCUUGCAAAUUUCAGGUGAUGAUACAGAAGCUGUAGAACAUACUGAAAUGCAAGGCUUCAACAGUGUAAAGAGAUAAAUUAUUCAUGUAAAAGUAUUUCAAGUAGUGAUGAUUUAAUUACAUUGUUCGAUGUUUGUACAGGAGUAAGCAUGUAUUUUUAUCAAUUUAACACAGAUCAAAGGAGAUGAAGGGACAUUCUGCCAUGACAUACACUUAACCAAAACUAUUCAAAAUGAAAACCGGAUUUCAAAUAACCAGACACCAAGAUGCAGGGCCCUUAUUUUAAACCUUUUUAUUUGGUUAGAGUGAUAUGUAUUUAGCCAUAGAUGGAGAAACAAAGCUCAGGGUUUGUUGAAUUAGCAUGAGAGAAAAUUAUGUACCAACAGAAUUAUUUGUGAGAAGAAUGAACAAAUUUUGAUAAAGUAUGAAUUUGUUUUAUUUUAAAAAGCAAACAUACUAAAUUUUUUUUAUUUUAUUGCUUAUAAUUUAUUAAGAAUGUUUACACCUGUAUAAGGAUUUCAUAUAUACAUUGUAUGUGUGUAUAUAUAAAUACAUAUAUGACUGCCUAAAUUGUUUAUAAAUUUAAUUUUUCUUUAAUAGGUUUCAUUCCUUCAGAGCUCCAUUAAUGUAAUCAAAAUGAAAUAUAGAUUAGUUUAAAUGUGAAUUCAGUGACUCUAGGGCCAAAGAAUAUUAGGUAUGUUUGGAAAGAAUUUUUGUAUUUAUUCCUGUUACAGUUUUGACUUUCAACUUCUCUCCCCGUGCAUGGAAGUCCUGGUAAAGGAUCUAACAUCUUUAUUCCCUUCUUUCCUCUUCCAGCUGAGCAGAGUUGGAUAAUUGAAUUAGUCAUUCUGACAUUCUUUGGACCAUAUCAUCUUAGUGGUUUGGGGUCAGUGCUCAUCUGAUAUAUCUUUCUUACCACCUCUUCUACUUACUUUCUCUUACUUAAAUUAUCUGGCAUAAGCAGUUAUCUCCAGCUUUUGUUAGAAUCUUGCAUGUUGAUUACUAAAACUAUACUUUGUUUCCCAUUUAUUUAUUACCCUUUUGCAUGUAUUUGUGUGACAGGGAACUCUGCAGCAGGGGGUGACUGACACACCAAACAAGAUGUUUCACUGGGUACUCUGCCAUAGAAAUGGCAGAUUAAGAAGAUUGACUAUACCAAACAUUAUAUUAAAAACACAAAAUAAAAACUAUAAAAAUGUACUUUAGGACAUUAAAGAAAACUCAAGUUAGAAGCAUACCAUUUUCCUUUCAUGGAAGGGUACAGUAUUACAAAGAUAAUUUGUUUAACUUGAUUUAUUAAAUUCUAGUUAUGUGCCCUAUAAUGAUGUUUCAGUCAGUGACAGACCUCAUAUAUGGCAGUGGUUCCAUAAGAUUACAAUACUGUAUUUUUACUGUACCUUCUUUAUGUUUAGAUAUGCAAGUACUUACCAUUGUGUUACAGUGUCCUACAGUAUUCACUACAAUAAUAUGCUGUACAGGUUUGUAGCCUAGGAGCAAUAGGCCAUAGCUUAGGUGUAUAGUAGAUCAUACCAUCUAGGUUUGUGUAAGUACACUCUGUGAUUGUACAAUUUUAAAAUCUCCUAAUGAUGAUGCAUUUCUCAGAAUGUAUCCCCUUUGCUAAGCAAUGCAUGACUGCAAUCCUAAUUCUCACAUGUUUUGGGGAAAAAAUUUUAAUUUUGAAAAAAUUUAGGAAAGUUCCUACCAAAUAUACAUGUAUAAAGUUUAUUAAAAGUCAUAAUGACCCAGGAAUAGCUAAUGACACAGAAGUAGAUCAAAAUAGAACACAAUAGAGAACUUCAAAAUAAAACAGGUGUGAGAAUUGUGUGUGUGAAAAAGCUGGGUUCAAAUAAGUUGGUUUGUUAGACAUUCAUAUGCCUACCCAUCAGCCAUUUCGUUCUCCCUUCCUUGCUGACAAAGCCCCAUUUUUUUUUUCUUUUUUUUUGGCCUAAAACUCUGUAUGGCUGCCUUGUGCUAUAGAAUAGGGUGCUUCCCUAGCCUAGAGAGGGUGAGUGUUGAUUAGAUUCUGUGCCAAUCAUGGUAAUUGGCUUACUUGAUCAUUUGAUGGAAUCUAGGCUAACGAGACAAAGGAAGUCUGAAGGCUUUGAAUAAGAAAUUUUCUGUUGCUCUUAACAAUUGAUACAAGUUAGGGAUUUGCCAGCAUCCCUCUUCUGCUUCUCAGUGAAGAUAUGUGAUAUGGAUGUUUGAAGCUAAUCUGCAACAGCCUUCUGAUGGCCAUGAAAGGACAAGUAUGGAGAUGAAAGCUAUCACACUGAGAAUAGUGGGAUGUAGAUAGAAAGCACCUGAAUUGUGCUUCUGAAUUAACCAAUCCAGGAACUGCUUUACCUUUGGACUUUUUGUUAUGUGAGAUAUUCUUUAUAUUGUUCCAUUUGCUUUGGGUAUAUGUAUAUUGUUACUUGUAGCCAAAAAGAAACCUCUCUUAGUAGAAACAAAGGGAGAGUUAGGUUAUUCAAAAAUUAGUAUGGGACAAUUGAAUAUGCCUUUUUCUGCGGGAGUAGGUGGGGAGAAACUUAAAGGUUCACUUGUAAAACAAUAAAGUACUAAAGAAAAUGUGA